AUGGAGAAUAGGAAUAACAUGACAGAGUUUGUUUUGCUGGGGCUUACAGAGAAUCCAAAGAUGCAGAAAAUCAUAUUUGUUGUGUUUUUUGUCAUCUAUAUCAUCACUGUGGUGGGAUAUGUGCUCAUUGUGGUCACCAUCACUGCCAGCCCAUCACUGGGGUCCCCCAUGUACCUUUCCCUGGCCUAUCUCUCCUUUAUUGAUGCCUGCUAUUCCUCUGUCAAUACCCCUAACCUGAUCACACAUUCACUCUAUGGAAAGAAGGCCAUCCUAUUCAAUGGAUGCAUGACUCAAGUCUUUGGAGAACAUUUCUUCGGAGGUGCAGAGGGCAUCCUACUUACUGUGAUGGCCUAUGACCACUAUGUGGCCAUCUGCAAGCCCUUGCACUAUAUGACUAUCAUGAACCAGUGUGUGUGUGCCCUGCUAAUGGGAGUGGUGUGGAUGGGAGGCUUUCUUCAUGCAACCAUACAGAUCCUCUUCAUCUUCCAAUUACCUUUCUGUGGUCCUAAUGUCAUAGAUCACUUUAUGUGUGAUCUGAACCCUUUGCUCAACCUCGCCUGCACUGACACCCAUAUGCUGGAACUCUUCAUUGCUGCCAACAGUGGAUUCAUCUGCUUGUUAAACUUUGCCCUCCUGCUGGUCUCCUAUGUGGUCAUCUUGUGCUCCCUAAGGACUCAUAGCUUGGAGGCAAGGCACAAAGCCCUCUCCACCUGUGUCUCCCACAUCACGGUUGUCAUCUUAUUCUUUGUGCCCUGCAUAUUUGUGUACAUGAGACCUGCAGCUACUUUACCUAUUGAUAAAGCAGUUGCUAUAUUCUACACUAUGAUAACUCCUAUGUUAAACCCCUUAAUCUAUACCUUGAAGAAUGCCCAGAUGAAAAAUGCCAUCAGGAAAUUGUGUAGUAGAAAGGACAUUUCAGGUGACAAAUAA